AGUCUCCUAGGCAACCCCGCUAAACAAGAUGGCGACCUCCGAGAGGGCUCUCCUGAGGACCAGAGCUGCCUCUCUCCUGAGAGGCUUGGGCAGAUCCCGAACUGGAGCCCGAUCGUUACAGUUUCGCGCAGAAAAAGAGCGUCAGCCUUGCUGGUCUUUUCCCAUGGGGCAGAAGACGAAAGGCAGCUCUAACAUAGCCUCCUCCUACCUGCUCCAGCAGCUCAUGCACCGCUAUCAGGAGCUGGACUCGGACGGAGAUGAGGACCAGGGCGAGGGCGAGGCGGGAUCCGAGGAGUCCUCAGAGUCCGAAAUGCUGAAUUUGGAGGAGGAAUUUGAUGGGGUCCUGAGAGAGGAGGCUGUGGCCAAAGCACUCCAUCACUUGGGGCGCUCAGGCUCUGGGACUGAGCAAGUCUACCUCAAUCUAACUUUAUCAGGUUGUAAUUUAAUUGAUGUUAGCAUUCUCUGUGGAUAUGUUCAUCUACAGAAGUUGGAUCUUUCAGCGAAUAAAAUUGAAGAUUUAUCUUGUGUGAGUUGUAUGCCUUAUCUCCUAGAACUUAAUGCUUCUCAAAAUAAUUUGACUACGUUCUUCAAUUUCAAGCCACCCAAAAACCUCAAGAAGGCGGAUUUUUCCCACAACCAAAUUUCUGAAAUUUGUGAUUUGUCAGCGUAUCAUGCUCUCACUAAACUAAUUUUGGAUGGCAAUGAGAUAGAAGAAAUCAGUGGACUAGAGAUGUGCAACAACCUAAUUCACCUUAGUUUGGCCAACAAUAAGAUCACGACAAUUAAUGGCUUAAACAAGUUACCAAUCAAAAUACUUUGUCUGAGCAAUAACCAGAUUGAGAUGAUCACAGGUUUGGAGGAUCUGAAAGCCCUGCAGAACCUGGAUCUGUCCCACAAUCAGAUAAGCAGCCUCCAAGGCUUAGAGAAUCAUGACCUCCUGGAAGUGAUCAACCUGGAGGAUAAUAAGAUUGCUGAGCUGAGAGAAAUAGAAUACAUUAAAAAUUUACCCAUCCUUCGAGUUCUCAAUCUUCUAGAAAAUCCAAUUCAGGAAAAGUCUGAAUAUUGGUUCUUCGUAAUUUUUAUGCUUCUGCGAUUAACAGAAUUAGAUCAGAAGAAGAUUAAAGUGGAAGAAAAGGUUUCAGCAGUGAAUAAAUAUGAUCCUCCCCCUGAAGUGGUUGCAGCUCAAGACCACCUGACCCAUGUUGUCAACAGCGUGAUGCAGCCGCAGAGGAUCUUUGACAGCACUCUUCCCAGCCUGGAUGCCCCUUAUCCCAUGCUGAUACUAGCUGGUCCUGAAGCUUGUGGGAAACGAGAGCUUGCCCAUCGCCUCUGCAGACAGUUUAGCACUUACUUCAGAUAUGGGGCCUGUCAUACCACAAGACCACCUUACUUUGGAGAAGGGGAUCGAGUUGAUUAUCAUUUUAUCUCUCAAGACGUUUUUGAUGAAAUGGUGAACAUGGGGAAAUUCAUUCUAACAUUUAGUUAUGGUAAUCACAAGUAUGGAUUAAAUAGGGACACCGUAGAAGGUAUCGCAAGAGAUGGUUUGGCAAGCUGUAUUCAUAUGGAAAUAGAAGGUGUAAGAAGUUUGAAAUAUUCCUAUUUUGAGCCUCGUUAUAUCCUGGUGGUGCCCAUGAACAAGGAAAAAUAUGAGGGAUAUUUGCGGAGAAAAGGAUUAUUCAGUCGUGCAGAAAUUGAAUUUGCUGUCUCCAGAGUGGACCUUUAUAUUAAAAUUAAUCAGAAUUUUCCGGGAUAUUUUGAUGAGGUAAUCAAUGCAGAUGAUCUGGAUGUUGCCUACCAAAAACUGAGUCAGCUCAUUAGAGAAUACCUUGGAUUGACUGAGGAACCUGCCAAGAGUUUGGCUACAACUGCAGCAGGAGCUCCCGCUAGCAAGAAGACUGUCUCUGGGGUGCCAGCACACCUGGUUCCAUCUCCCAGGUGCUUGGCGAAACUGCAAGCAGAUGGCCAGAUGACAGAGCAUCUCUCUGGAAUGCAAAUUCAUGCCAAGGACCUAGAAAAUCAGAGCGUAACUCCUGCCCAGAACCAAGAGCUGGCUCAGGAUGGAGAAACCCAUCAAAAAGAGCUUUCUCCUGACAGCCAUCUCAAUCCUGAGCUCCCUCAACACCUCAGUUCAUCAGCACUGGGUCUUCCUCAGCAGGCCCAGGACCUAUCCCUAAACCCAACGGAAGAGGAUGUCCAACAAUCAGAUCUUCCCCUAAAACAAAUAGCCACUGAGACAGAUGUCCCUGAGGUGGAAGCCAGUGAGGUUGGGCAGUCUCCCAUCACCCCGACCCUGGUGCCUCCUGUGCACCCUUCCCCUCCCUCGUCCCGCAGCCCUCAGCCAGGCCAGGACAAGGAGUCAGGGGAGGCCCAGGUAACCCCUACUGGCCCUCCUCUGUCUGAACCUCUACAGGGACCUGGCCCCACUCCCCUCAGCCCUCAGAGAAUUCAGGAUGAGGAAAUUGAGUCAGACAAACUUCCACCCAGCAGUUCCCACCAUGAUCCUCCAAAAGAUUCUUCCCACACUGACUUGGUGCAGAAACUUGCUGGCGAUUCUCAGCAAGCUCUGAAGGAGGAAACCUCCAAACCGGAAGCCAUCCGAGUCAGUAUCCCUCACCCAGAACUGCCACAUCCCCAAGACUUAGCAACAGAUACCAAGCAGCCCCAGGCCAGGGGAGCCCCGGGGACCUUGCUUCCUAGAAGCCGGCUGGCUCCCACUCGGCUGCCCCAGCCUCAGGUGCUGGCUCCCCUCCAGAGCAGGAGGCCCACACCCAAACUCCUAUCGCCCAGCAGGGAAGAGGCUUUAGGAACAACCUCCCAUCAAACCAUGACGGUCUCUCCCAGGCUUCCACCAACCCGGGAAGCAGACACCAGUAAACUUCCUCCCAUCAGCCCUCCGCACUCAAAACCACCACCAAAUCUGAGCCCCCAGGCAGCCCACAGUCUUCAGCAAGUCCAGGAAGAGAAGGUCAGUGAGGUGAAACUCCCUCUUAUCAGUCCCCCCAGCCAGGAGCAAGCAGAACCUCGCAUCCUCAGUCCCGCCCAGGAGGAGGCGGCUCAGAAAGUGAGGCUCCCUCGCAUUCCUGCUCCUCUUCCGGAGCCAGGGCUGCCCCAGAACUCGGGGACUCAGCCUGAUCCAAGGCCUGCAAAGGAAAGGAAAGCUCCCCAAGCAGGCAGCUCCUCCAGGAGGAAGAUUCCAGACAUGCGGGCCUCACCCCACAACCAGGGGCCACUUCAGCAGACAGGGGCUAGGGAAAAAAAGCUCCCCAACCAGAAAGGGACGGCUAGAGGACUGGCACCUCUGGAAGAGGCACCACCUGGGAACCACCAGCCAGCCUUGCAGCUAGAACCCCACGAUCAGCCAGCUCCCACCAUGGUGCCCGACGAUCCCAACCCCAGCCCUCCUCUUGUUUCUUGUCUAAGCUAGUAUUUCAGUGUGUAACUGUUACAAAUUAGGCCAUCUGAGCAACCAGAGAAGCAAAGUCCAUACACCAGAAAUUCCUGAGCCGCCCCACGCCGAGCCAUCACCUAAGACCCCCAAUUACAAGAAGAUUAAAAAAAACAUAAUUCCAGGAAAAGGACCCAUACCAACCUCCCCACAAAUGACCUGGCUUGGAAUGUAGAUGUGUCCAAACAAGGGCCAUCUUGUAAGAGAGAGAUUUUUGGAGGGUUAUCUCAAGAAAAUAAAACUCCCGUCAAUGGUGAUCAGCCAGCUCAGGAGGGCCAGCCCUCACCCGGGAGACCUCUCCAGAGGGAAAAGGCCCCUGCGGAGUCGCUACAGGAUAGCUCGGCUCCUGUGGAGCAUCCAGGGAGAAAGGGACAGGUUCAUCGAAAGGGCAGGUCUCAGAGGAGAGAGAUUGCUUCGCAAUCCCCAGAGCAGGACAGUGAGCCCCCAACCCAGCAGCCUGUCAAAGACACACCAGCCCAUCAGGGGAGAGGUCAGGCCAGAGAGAGCUCUGUCCAAAGGCACAAUGCACUUGCUUCCAAGCAGCAAACCAAAGAGAAGCGAACCUGAAAACAUGGGGCAGUGCCACAGGACAAAAGCCCCGCCACUCCCCAGAACCAGGUGUCUACUGUGGAGCAGGGCAGCUGGAAGGGAAGACUGCGCCCCAGGAGCAGUCAGAGCACCAAGGUUUAAGCCAUCCCUGGAGCCACCAGCUCAUUAAGGUCUGGGAACCCCGAGGCAGCACUGUCACAGAACGACCAGCUAUGGCUGGGUCCUGUGAGUCUCCACACUGGCUUCCUCCUGAACCCAUGGUCAGCGUAGGUGGAGGGGCUGUUCAGCACUGUCCAAACCUUGGAUUCCUAGAAGGCAGCCAAUCUGCACUCCUGUGCCUCUUCUGCUGUUGCCGUCACAGCCUGGAAGAGCAGUUGUUGCAGAGGGAUGCAGCUCUAUCAGCUGCUGCCACCAAAUUGAGCCAUUCUGGAAGGCUGGUGUCAGCAAGUAGCCUUUGUGUCCAGACACGAAUCCAACCUGAGUUCCAACUCUGGCUGAAGCAGGGCCAUAUUGCCAUUAAGUUUUCUUCUCUUCAUAAGGAAAAUUCGCUUCUAGACUUCUAGAAAAUUCUCUCACCCCUCUUGCAUUAUCGAGGAGUUCCAAAGCAAAAAGAACUUUUGAGACAGGAAGACUUUGCUGUUCCUGGAGGUUCCAAACCUACAGUUAACUUGUGGGAAUCUUCUGUAGGGAAGAAGACAUAUUUUGCAUGCAUGACUCUGUGAUCAAAUGCUUCAGAUUUGUCUUGGCAAUAUGUUGCCUGAAACUUACUUUUGCUUGAAAUGUAUUUCAAAAUGAAUACCUUCCUUCUUUCUCUGAAUAGAAAUCUCAUGUAAAUUAGCUCAUGCCUUUAUUAUGCCAAACCAUCUGGUUGAAUCAAUUAAAAGAAUUAAUGGGGAGAACAUUUAAGUGAAUCAGUUGUUCGUUUAUCUAUUCAUACCAUCAGGAUUCUUUCGCUGGCAAAUGAUAGGAGUCCACUCUAAGCCAGCUUCUGUGACUCUAUUAGAAGGGAGUAGAAGAUUUCAUAUGAACAAACUAUGGGAAGGGCAGGGCUACAGCAAGUCUCAGAGAGACUGGGGGCCAGUUGUGGAACAUAACCAGGACUCUAGUCAUCUCCUGGACUCUGGUCUAGGACUCUCACCACUUCUCUUCUCUGUUUCUUUCUCCAUGUUGGCUUCAUUCUUUGGACUACAGAUGACUCUAUCAGUUUCUGCACAUGGUGGGAAACAUGGUUACCAGCAGCUCUCAAGCCCAUAUCUGAUUUUACCUCUGGAAGCUCCCACUACUGUAAAGGGAUUAAUUUGAAUGAAUGUUCAUUAAUCCUAAUCCAAAGAAAGUCUUGUUGGCCUAGCUUGGUUUAGGCACUUGUUCUUAAACCAAUCUACUCUGGCAAGGACCAGGGUUACCUUCAGACAUACCUAUUGAACCUACUCCUAUGUAUGGACACUAUACUCCACCCAAAAAGAGGAUAAUUGUGACUGAAACGGACAACUCAAGAUGUGACUCUUAAAAAGCUGCAAGAUAUCUAUUGAGCACUUACUGUGUACACAGCAGCAUGCUAAACUGUAUUUGGUAUCUCAUAUUUAAAAAUGUAACUGAUGACUAAAUGCCUGUGUAAAUGUCUCUUACACAAAAGAGAGGUGUCUAUGAAACUAUGAAUUUCAAAUGUUAUUUCAAGGGCAGUAGAGGAAACUGAUAUUUUAGAAAUCCAGGAUAUAGAAAUCCUCUUGCAAAAUGAAGAGCUUAUAUAAUGCCAGUAAUUGCCCUCUGAUUUAUCUGAUUUGUCCAUGAUGAAAAUAAUACAGUAAUUGUAGAAAAUAUAUCAUUUGUUUAUUUUUA